UGCGCGCCGACCUGCAGCUGGGACCCGCGCCUGGAACCCUCCCGACGAGCGCAGGUGAGCGCCUCCUGCCAAGUGGGGCGGCGCCACACGGGCGUCCUGGGUGUCCCCCUGAGCUCCUUCCGCAGCUCAGGCCAACCCCCGCCCUGACCCGGUGGAGCCCCGGGACAGGGUGCGGACCCCGUUCCUUCGCGCUCCGAACCGGACGGACCCGCAGGAGGACCCCACGCCCGCUCCGCUCCGACCCCGCCGUCCCGCGCAGGCUGCGGUGACCCAGGCCGGCAGCCCAGGAUGGCGGCCCAGGUGACUCUGGAGGACGCGCUGUCCAACGUGGACCUCCUGGAGGAGCUGCCCCUGCCUGACCAGCAGCCCUGCAUCGAGCCCCCGCCAUCCUCGCUGCUCUACCAGCCAAAUUUCAACACUAACUUUGAAGACAGAAAUGCAUUUGUUACUGGCAUCGCAAGAUACAUUGAACAAGCCACCGUCCACUCUAGCAUGAACGAGAUGCUGGAGGAGGGCCAAGAAUAUGCUGUCAUGCUGUACACCUGGAGGAGCUGCUCCCGGGCCAUCCCACAGGUGAAAUGUAACGAGCAGCCUAACAGAGUGGAAAUCUACGAGAAAACCGUGGAGGUUCUGGAGCCUGAGGUCACAAAACUGAUGAAUUUCAUGUACUUCCAGAGAAAUGCCAUUGAGCGUUUCUGCGGGGAAGUGAGGCGCCUGUGCCAUGCCGAGAGGAGGAAGGACUUCGUGUCAGAAGCCUACCUGAUCACACUGGGCAAAUUCAUCAACAUGUUCGCUGUGCUGGACGAGCUGAAGAACAUGAAGUGCAGUGUGAAGAACGACCACUCAGCGUACAAGAGGGCCGCUCAGUUUUUACGUAAAAUGGCAGAUCCACAGUCCAUCCAGGAAUCGCAGAAUCUGUCCAUGUUCCUGGCCAAUCAUAACAAGAUCACACAGUCUCUGCAGCAGCAGCUCGAAGUGAUUUCUGGCUACGAAGAGCUCCUGGCAGAUAUUGUGAAUCUGUGUGUGGAUUACUACGAGAACAGGAUGUAUUUGACGCCCAGUGAGAAACACAUGCUUCUCAAAGUCAUGGGAUUUGGUCUGUACCUGAUGGAUGGGAGUGUCAGUAACAUCUAUAAGUUGGAUGCCAAGAAAAGAAUAAACUUAUCCAAAAUCGACAAGUACUUCAAGCAACUCCAGGUGGUUCCGCUAUUUGGGGACAUGCAAAUAGAACUGGCAAGAUAUAUCAAGACCAGCGCCCACUACGAGGAAAAUAAAUCUCGAUGGACGUGCACAUCCUCCGGCAGCAGCCCUCAGUACAACAUCUGCGAGCAGAUGAUCCAGAUCCGCGAGGACCACAUGCGCUUCAUUUCGGAGCUGGCGCGCUACAGCAACAGCGAGGUGGUCACGGGCUCGGGCCGCCAGGAGGCCCAGAAGACGGACGCGGAGUACCGCAAGCUCUUCGACCUGGCGCUGCAGGGCCUGCAGCUGUUGUCGCAGUGGAGCGCGCACGUGAUGGAAGUGUAUUCCUGGAAGCUUGUGCACCCCACCGACAAGUACUCCAACAAGGACUGCCCCGACAGCGCUGAAGAGUACGAGCGUGCCACGCGCUACAACUACACCAGCGAGGAGAAGUUUGCCCUAGUGGAGGUGAUCGCCAUGAUCAAAGGCCUGCAGGUGCUGAUGGGCAGGAUGGAGAGCGUGUUCAACCACGCCAUCCGGCACACCGUCUAUGCCGCACUGCAGGACUUCUCCCAGGUGACCCUUAGGGAGCCGCUGCGGCAGGCCAUCAAGAAGAAGAAGAACGUCAUCCAGAGUGUCCUGCAGGCCAUCAGGAAGACCGUGUGUGACUGGGAGACGGGGCAUGAGCCCUUCAAUGACCCAGCCUUGCGGGGCGAGAAGGACCCCAAGAGCGGCUUCGACAUAAAAGUACCACGCCGCGCCGUGGGACCCUCCAGCACUCAGCUUUACAUGGUGAGAACCAUGCUAGAGUCCCUCAUUGCAGACAAAAGUGGUUCCAAGAAAACCUUGAGAAGUAGCCUUGAGGGGCCCACCAUAUUGGACAUAGAAAAAUUUCAUCGAGAGUCAUUCUUCUACACUCACUUGAUAAAUUUCAGUGAAACGCUGCAGCAGUGCUGUGACCUUUCGCAGCUGUGGUUCCGAGAGUUCUUCCUGGAGCUGACCAUGGGCAGGAGGAUCCAGUUCCCCAUUGAGAUGUCGAUGCCCUGGAUCCUGACGGACCACAUCCUGGAGACCAAGGAGGCAUCGAUGAUGGAGUACGUGCUCUACUCCCUGGACCUGUACAAUGACAGCGCCCACUACGCGCUCACCAGGUUCAACAAGCAGUUCCUGUACGACGAAAUUGAGGCCGAGGUGAAUCUAUGUUUUGACCAAUUUGUUUACAAGCUAGCAGACCAGAUAUUUGCCUAUUAUAAGGUUAUGGCAGGAAGUUUGCUUCUUGAUAAACGGUUACGAUCAGAAUGCAAGAAUCAGGGAGCCACGAUCCACCUCCCGCCGUCUAACCGCUACGAGACGCUGCUGAAGCAGAGGCAUGUGCAGCUCCUCGGCAGAUCAAUAGACCUCAAUCGUCUGAUCACCCAGCGCGUCUCAGCAGCCAUGUAUAAGUCCCUAGAACUGGCGAUUGGACGAUUUGAAAGUGAAGAUUUGACCUCCAUAGUUGAGCUGGAUGGCCUGUUGGAAAUCAACCGCAUGACCCACAAGCUGCUGAGCCGGUACCUGACGCUGGACAGCUUCGACGCCAUGUUCCGGGAGGCCAACCACAACGUGUCAGCGCCCUACGGGAGGAUCACCCUGCACGUCUUCUGGGAGCUCAACUAUGACUUCCUGCCCAACUACUGCUACAACGGCUCUACCAACCGGU